GUUAGUGGGUCCCAACGGCUGCAGGCGGGGCCGGCGGGGGCGCAGCGGCCCGGGAGGUGCGUGGUUGAGCGAAGCCGCGGGGCCCAACCGCAGUCGCGGGGUCUGGGAGGAGACCUGAAUGAAAUGAGGGAGCCUUGGGAGCAUGAUCCAGGCGGAGGGAACUGGAUUCGGGAGGAGGAACUGCCUUGGCCUUGAAAGAUACCUACCAGGAGUUCAAGUGCUGUGCGGGUGCAUCAGCUUUGUAGAUUUGUGCAAGAUGAAAAUUGGAAUUGUCUUAGGAAAUUAUGGAUCAUUCAUUUAUUCAGUGCUGGAUUCAUUCAGUGAUUUAUGUCUGAAGUGUGACAGAAGGGGAGUAAGGCCAAGUGUCCUUGCCCUCUAUUGGAGAUUCUGCCUCCCCUGGGACAGAUGGCUUCUUGAGCACACUCCCACGAUGGGUGGCUGCUCUGGUACAUCUCAUCCACUUCUUCAUCUGUGAAGCUGUCACCCAUGGUGGUGAGCAGCUCCUGGAGGUGGUCCUCAUGAAUGAAACCUGAGGAUUCCUCGUUGAAGCAGGUAUUCAUCCAUGGGGUUCUUCCGCGGUGAAGCCAGCUUGUCGUGCUGUCCCCCUUGUCAUUGAAGCCAUCAUGGUUCUGGUCAAUCAUGUUGAAAGCCUCCUUAAACUCCUGGAUGUGGAACUGGUCGAACAUCACGAAGACAUUGGAUGUGGCCCCUUGUGCUGUGGUCGCUUCUUGGUGGUCUUGGCUUUGGUCCACUUGCUGAACAUUUUGGCUUCAGGAAGCAGUACCUUGAAGAGAAAUUGGAGAGGGAGUCAAUUCCUAGGAUAGCAGAGAGAUGGACAACAGACAGAAUAGAUGGAGUUUCACAAUGGUGGCCAUGUGUCUGGAAUUGGUGGGUUCUUGGUCUCACUGACUUCAAGAAUGAAGCCGCACACCCUCGCAGUCACCCCAGCUCUGAUCUUUGCCAUCACAGUUGCUACAAUCGGCUCUUUCCAGUUUGGCUACAACACUGGGGUCAUCAAUGCUCCUGAGACGAUCAUAAAGGAAUUUAUCAAUAAAACUUUGACGGACAAGGCAAAUGCCCCUCCCUCUGAGGUGCUGCUCACGAAUCUCUGGUCCUUGUCUGUGGCCAUAUUUUCCGUCGGGGGUAUGAUCGGCUCCUUUUCCGUCGGACUCUUUGUUAACCGCUUUGGCAGGCGCAAUUCAAUGCUGAUUGUCAACCUGUUGGCUGCCACUGGUGGCUGCCUUAUGGGACUGUGUAAAAUAGCUGAGUCAGUUGAAAUGCUGAUCCUGGGCCGCUUGGUUAUUGGCCUCUUCUGCGGACUCUGCACAGGUUUUGUGCCCAUGUACAUUGGAGAGAUCUCGCCUACUGCCCUGAGGGGUGCCUUUGGCACUCUCAACCAGCUGGGCAUAGUUAUUGGAAUUCUGGUGGCCCAGAUCUUUGGUCUGGAACUCAUCCUUGGGUCUGAAGAGCUAUGGCCGGUGCUAUUAGGCUUUACCAUCCUUCCAGCUAUCCUGCAAAGUGCAGCCCUUCCAUGUUGCCCUGAAAGUCCCAGAUUUUUGCUCAUUAACAGAAAAAAAGAGGAGAAUGCUACGCGGAUCCUCCAGCGGUUGUGGGGCACCCAGGAUGUAUCCCAAGACAUCCAGGAGAUGAAAGAUGAGAGUGCAAGGAUGUCACAAGAAAAGCAAGUCACCGUGCUGGAGCUCUUUAGAGUGUCCAGCUACCGACAGCCCAUCAUCAUUUCCAUUGUGCUCCAGCUCUCUCAGCAGCUCUCUGGGAUCAAUGCUGUGUUCUAUUACUCAACAGGAAUCUUCAAGGAUGCAGGUGUUCAACAGCCCAUCUAUGCCACCAUCAGCGCGGGUGUGGUUAAUACUAUCUUCACUUUACUUUCUCUAUUUCUGGUGGAAAGGGCAGGAAGAAGGACUCUGCAUAUGAUAGGCCUUGGAGGGAUGGCUUUUUGUUCCACGCUCAUGACUGUUUCUUUGUUAUUAAAGAAUCACUAUAAUGGGAUGAGCUUUGUCUGUAUUGGGGCUAUCUUGGUCUUUGUGGCCUGUUUUGAAAUUGGACCAGGCCCCAUUCCCUGGUUUAUUGUGGCCGAACUCUUCAGCCAGGGCCCCCGCCCAGCUGCGAUGGCAGUGGCCGGCUGCUCCAACUGGACCUCCAACUUCCUAGUCGGAUUGCUCUUCCCCUCUGCUGCUUACUAUUUAGGAGCCUACGUUUUUAUUAUCUUCACCGGCUUCCUCAUUACCUUCUUGGCCUUUACCUUCUUCAAAGUCCCUGAGACCCGUGGCAGGACUUUUGAGGAUAUCACACGGGCCUUUGAAGGGCAGGCACACGGUGCAGAUAGAUCUGGGAAGGACGGCGUCAUGGGGAUGAACAGCAUCGAGCCUGCUAAGGAGACCACCACCAAUGUCUAAGUCAUGCCUCCUUCCACCUCCCUCCCGGCAUGGGAAAGCCACCUCUCCCUCAACAAGGGAGAGACUUUAUCAGGAUGAACCCAGGACUGCUUCUGAAUGCUGCUACUUGAUUUCUUUCUCAUCCCACGCACUCCAUGAGCACCCCAAGGCUGCAGUUUGUUGGAUCUUCAAUGGCUUUUUAAAUUUUAUUUCCUGGACAUCCUCUUCUGCUUAGGAGAGACCGAGUGAACCUACCUUCAUUUCAGGAGGGAUUGGCCGCUUGGCACAUGACAACUUUGCCAGCUUUUCCUCCCUUGGGUUCUGAUAUUGCCGCACUAGAGGAUAUAGGAGAGGAAAAGUAAGGUGCAGUUGCCCCAACCUCAGACUUACCAGGAAGCAGAUACAUAUGAGUGUGGAAGCCGGAGGGUGUUUAUGUAAGAGCACCUUCCUCACUUCCAUACAGCUCUACGCGGCAAAUUAACUUGAGUUUUAUUUAUCUUAUCCUCUGGUUUAAUUACAUAAAUAUUUAUUUUUUAAGUGUAAUUUUGCCAAAUAAUAAAAACAGAAGGAAAUUGAGAUUAGAGGGAGGUGUUUAAAGAGAGGUUAUAGAGUAAAAGAUUUGAUGCUGGAGAGGUUAAGGUGCAAUAAGAAUUCAGGGAGAAAUGUUGUUCAUUAUUGGAGGGUAAAUGAUGUGGUGCCUGAGGUCUGUACAUUACCUCUUAACAAUUUCUGUCCUUCAGAUGGAAACUCUUUGAUUUCUCAGAAAAGUUGUAUGCCUAUUUAAUAAAGCUACUCAUUUCCUUUGGAACUUUAUCUUUAAGAUAAUAGUUUACAUGUAGUAGUACUUGAAAUCUAGGAUUAUUAACUAAUAUGGGCAUUGUAGUUAAUGGCGGUUGAUGGGUUCUAAUUUUGGAUGGAGUCCAGGGAAGAGAAAGUGAUUUCUAGAAAGCCUGUUCCCCUCACUGGACGAAAUAACUCCUUGUAGUAGUCUCAUUACUUUUGAAGUAAUCCCGCCACCUAUCUAGUGGGAGAGCCAUCCAAAUGAGAAACCUAAAAUAAUUGGUUCUUGGUAGAGAUUCAUUAUUUCUCCACUUUGUUCUUUAGGAGAUUUUAGGUGUUGAUUUUCUGUUUUAUUUUAACUCAUACCUUUAAAGGAAUUCCCCAAAGAAUGUUUACAGCAAACUUGGAAUUUGUAACCUCAGCUCUGGGAGAGGAUUUUUUUCUGAGCGAUUAUUAUCUAAAGUGUGUUGUUGCUUUAGGCUCACGGCACGCUUGCGUAUGUCUGUUACCAUGUCACUGUGGUCCUAUGCCGAAUGCCCUCAGGGGACUUGAAUCUUUCCAAUAAACCAGGUUUAGACAGUAUGAGUCAAUGUGCAGUGCAGCCCACACUUGAGAGGAUGAAUGUAUGUGCACUGUCACUUUGCUCUGGGUGGAAGUAUGUUAUUGUUGACUUAUUUUCUCUGUGUUUGUUCCUACAGCCCCUUUUUCAUAUGUUGCUCAGUCUCCCUUUCCCUUCUUGGUGCUUACACAUCUCAGACCCUUUAGCCAAACCCUUGCCAGUGACAGUAUUUUGGUUCUCAGUUCUCACUGUUCCCUCUGCUCCUGGAGCCUUUGAAUAAAAAUGCACGUAGCUAUGGAGUGGGGUUUAGCUGGAAAGGUGGCCUUCCAACUUCACGUCAACUUCUGGCUCCUCAGUUUGGCAGUAAGGCAGGGAAGUUGUUUUCCUAUUUCUCACUGAGAAGAUUGUGAAUAUUUCCAUAUGGAUUUUCCAUUAUUGUUUGUUUGAUUCUUUGUUUUAAAAUAAAAAUUCUGAAUGUACAUGA